AGAUCUUUUCCAGCAGCUGCUGCCUGCCAGAGAGGCGCCUUCAGAGACCCAGCGCUUACACAAUACCCACCAUGUCCCAGGCUGGUGCUCAGGAAGCCCCUAUCAAGAAGAAGCGCCCCCCUGUGAAGGACGAGGACCUGAAGGGGGCCCGAGGAAACCUGACCAAGAACCAGGAAAUCAAGUCCAAGACCUACCAGGUCAUGCGAGAGUGUGAGCAAGCUGGCUCGGCCGCCCCGUCGGUGUUCAGCCGCACCCGCACAGGUACCGAGACUGUCUUUGAGAAGCCCAAAGCCGGACCCACCAAGAGUGUCUUCGGCUGAGAAGUGUGCGCCACUCCCCUUGCUGCCCGAAUGCUCGGAAACAGGAGCCUUUCCCAGGAACUCUUUUUUAUGCCAGAACGCUUCCUCUCCCCUGCUGUCUCUGGGGCUGCCACCCUCCCCCACAGUCCAGGCCCUUCAGCCAAGGGCUCUGCACCAGCACCUUGGAAGCACCAAUAAAGAGGAUGCCCACGUGGCCCCAGCAA